GCACUUCCCGCUCGCCGGCCUCAGAGGCGGCGGGUCCGGCGCGGGCGCAGCGGUGCGGGCGCUCGGCUGGGGCGCGGGGCGGGGACGCGGCCGCUGCCCGCUUUGCGCCGCUCCUCCCUGCGCGAGUAGCGCUGGCCCCGGCGUCGAGGCGGCCAUGGCGACCCGGAGCCCGCUCCCCACCCACCCCGCCUGCUCCGCCCUCCCCUCCGCCCCGCGCCACCUUUGAUGGCUCGGACCUCAGCCGGCCACCGCCAGCCCUGCUCGCGCGCCCGCGCCGCCGCCGCCCGCGGGUAUUAAUAGCCGGCGCCGCCGCGCCCUCGGCCGCCGGGGGCUUGGGAGCCGCCGAUCCCGGAGCCCGAGCCGGGAGAGGGAGCCGCCGCAGCCGCCGGCGCUGUGGAGAUAUUCUCUAAGCCGCUUUCAUCAUGGGAGAAAUAGAGCAGAGGCCGACCCCAGGAUCACGACUGGGGGCCCCGGAAAAUUCGGGGAUCAGUACCUUGGAACGUGGACAGAAGCCGCCCCCAACACCUUCAGGAAAACUCGUGUCCAUCAAAAUCCAGAUGCUGGAUGACACCCAGGAGGCAUUUGAAGUUCCACAAAGAGCUCCUGGGAAGGUGCUGCUGGAUGCAGUUUGCAACCACCUCAACCUCGUGGAAGGUGACUAUUUUGGCCUCGAGUUUCCUGAUCACAAAAAGAUCACGGUGUGGCUGGAUCUCCUAAAACCCAUUGUGAAACAGAUUAGAAGGCCAAAGCACGUUGUUGUUAAGUUUGUGGUGAAAUUCUUUCCGCCUGACCACACACAACUCCAAGAAGAACUCACAAGGUACCUGUUCGCGCUGCAGGUGAAGCAGGACUUGGCUCAAGGCAGGUUGACGUGUAAUGACACCAGCGCAGCUCUCUUGAUUUCACACAUUGUGCAAUCUGAGAUUGGGGAUUUUGAUGAAGCCUUGGACAGAGAGCACUUAGCAAAAAAUAAAUACAUACCUCAGCAAGACGCACUAGAGGACAAAAUCGUGGAAUUUCACCAUAACCACAUUGGACAAACACCAGCAGAAUCAGAUUUCCAGCUCCUAGAGAUUGCCCGUCGGCUAGAGAUGUAUGGAAUCCGGUUGCACCCGGCCAAGGACAGGGAAGGCACGAAGAUCAAUCUGGCCGUUGCCAACACGGGAAUUCUAGUGUUUCAGGGUUUCACUAAGAUCAAUGCCUUCAACUGGGCCAAGGUGCGGAAGCUGAGCUUCAAGAGGAAGCGCUUUCUCAUCAAGCUCCGGCCAGAUGCCAAUAGUGCGUACCAGGAUACCUUGGAAUUCCUGAUGGCCAGUCGGGAUUUCUGCAAGUCCUUCUGGAAAAUCUGUGUUGAACAUCAUGCCUUCUUUAGACUUUUUGAAGAGCCCAAACCAAAGCCCAAGCCCGUCCUCUUUAGCCGGGGGUCAUCAUUUCGGUUCAGUGGUCGGACUCAGAAGCAGGUUCUCGACUAUGUUAAAGAAGGAGGACAUAAGAAGGUGCAGUUUGAAAGGAAGCACAGCAAGAUUCAUUCUAUCCGGAGCCUUGCUUCACAGCCUACAGAACUGAAUUCGGAAGUGCUGGAGCAGUCUCAGCAGAGCACCAGCCUUACAUUUGGAGAAGGUGCCGAAUCUCCAGGGGGCCAGAGCUGCCGGCGAGGAAAGGAACCGAAGGUUUCCGCCGGGGAGCCGGGGUCGCACCCGAGCCCUGCGCCGAGGAGAAGCCCCGCGGGUAACAAGCAGGCGGACGGAGCCGCCUCGGCGCCCACGGAGGAAGAGGAGGAGGUCGUUAAGGAUAGGACCCAGCAGAGUAAACCUCAGCCCCCGCAGCCAAGCACAGGCUCCCUGACUGGCAGUCCUCACCUUUCCGAGCUGUCUGUGAACUCGCAGGGGGGAGUGGCCCCUGCCAACGUGACCUUGUCUCCCAACCUGAGCCCCGACACCAAGCAGGCCUCUCCCUUGAUCAGCCCGCUGCUGAAUGACCAGGCCUGCCCCCGGACGGACGAUGAGGAUGAGGGCCGGAGGAAGAGAUUCCCAACUGAUAAAGCGUACUUCAUAGCUAAGGAAGUGUCUACCACCGAGCGAACAUAUCUGAAGGAUCUCGAAGUUAUCACUUCGUGGUUUCAGAGCACAGUGAGCAAAGAGGACGCCAUGCCGGAAGCACUGAAAAGUCUCAUAUUCCCGAAUUUUGAACCUUUGCACAAAUUUCAUACUAAUUUUCUCAAGGAAAUUGAGCAACGACUUGCCCUGUGGGAAGGCCGCUCAAAUGCCCAAAUCAGAGAUUACCAAAGAAUCGGCGAUGUCAUGCUGAAGAACAUUCAGGGCAUGAAGCACCUGGCGGCUCACCUGUGGAAGCACAGCGAGGCCUUGGAGGCCCUGGAGAAUGGAAUCAAGAGCUCCCGGCGGCUGGAGAACUUCUGCAGAGACUUUGAGCUGCAGAAGGUGUGUUACCUACCGCUCAACACCUUCCUCCUGCGGCCACUGCACCGGCUCAUGCACUACAAGCAGGUCCUGGAGCGGCUGUGCAAACACCACCCGCCGAGCCACGCCGACUUCAGGGACUGCCGAGCCGCUUUGGCAGAGAUCACGGAGAUGGUGGCACAGCUCCACGGUACGAUGAUCAAGAUGGAGAAUUUCCAGAAGCUGCACGAACUCAAGAAAGAUUUGAUUGGCAUUGACAAUCUUGUGGUUCCGGGAAGGGAGUUCAUCCGUCUGGGCAGCCUCAGCAAGCUCUCGGGGAAGGGGCUCCAGCAGCGCAUGUUCUUCCUGUUCAACGACGUCCUGCUAUACACGAGCCGGGGGCUGACGGCCUCCAAUCAGUUUAAAGUCCACGGGCAGCUCCCGCUCUAUGGCAUGACGAUUGAGGAGAGCGAAGACGAGUGGGGGGUGCCCCACUGCCUGACCCUCCGGGGCCAGCGGCAGUCCAUCAUCGUGGCCGCCAGUUCUCGGUCCGAGAUGGAGAAGUGGGUUGAGGACAUCCAGAUGGCCAUUGACCUGGCGGAGAAGAGCAGCAGCCCCGCCCCUGAGUUCCUGGCCAGCAGCCCCCCUGACAACAAGUCCCCUGAUGAAGCCACCGCGGCUGACCAGGAGUCAGAGGAUGACCUGAGCGCCUCGCGCACAUCGCUGGAGCGCCAGGCCCCGCACCGCGGCAACACAAUGGUGCACGUGUGCUGGCACCGCAACACCAGCGUCUCCAUGGUGGACUUCAGCAUCGCAGUGGAGAAUCAGUUGUCUGGAAACCUGCUGAGGAAAUUCAAAAACAGCAACGGGUGGCAGAAGCUGUGGGUGGUGUUCACAAACUUCUGCCUGUUCUUCUACAAAUCACACCAGGACAAUCAUCCCCUUGCCAGCCUGCCUCUGCUCGGCUACUCGCUCACCAUCCCCUCUGAGUCCGAGAACAUCCAGAAAGACUACGUGUUCAAGCUGCACUUCAAGUCCCACGUCUACUACUUCAGGGCGGAAAGCGAGUACACGUUCGAAAGGUGGAUGGAAGUGAUCCGCAGUGCCACCAGCUCUGCCUCGCGACCCCACGUGUUGAGUCACAAAGAGUCUCUUGUGUAUUGAUGGCCGGACACACUCGUUUCCGCAGUGGCUGCUUUCCUGGAAGACGUUUCCUUUCUUCUGUAUUAAUGAAGCCUGGUAAAAUUAACACCUGUCUGAAAAUCAAAAACAUGGCUUCCCAGCAGCUCUCCUGUCUCCACAGCCGCGUUUUUUAACCCCGACCUCUCAGCGUCUGAAUGAACAGCGCUCCCACCUCCAGUCCUGGCAUCCGCUGGGGGCGCUGUUCUUUAGCUAGUGCCAGUAUUAAAACAUUGUCAUUACGAGAGUGCCAAAUGACAUCUUCCCUCCACCCUGCCCCUGAAAAACAGUACACACACAUCCGUUCAACACAAGACAGGGCAAGUGUUUUUCUUCCUAAAAAAAGUUCUUUCUUUUAUUAUUUUCACCUAUUGGCUGCUGCAUUUUACGAAGUGGACUUCCCGGUGUUUGUUUGUUUGUUUGCAAUACACUCAGUGCAGCCUUAAGCAAAUGAGAUCAUUUUCAGAUUUCAUUUUUUUUUUCAGUCUUUCUACUUUUGUAAUAAUAGGAAGUUAGUAGGACUCACUUCUCUGAUUAAUAAGCAAUUUGCAGCACACAGCGUUCCACUGCGGGGUUUCACGCUCACCUGAAAACACCUGUUCCCAACCUACUUCUUGGUGCAAGUUGACCAAAUCGUUUUAAGUGGUAACUCUUUCCAACCGUAGCAGGGUUGUUUUCUGUUAAGCAAAGCCGAGAUCCAGUGCAAUACCUGGACUGUCACCGUCCUGUGAGUGGUGUACACAAUGGGAAGAUAAUAAGCCGUGGUGUUUUGCUGUCUGUCUGUGUCACAAGCAUGAAAACCCGUGUGUCAUUGAUCAGCACCAUUUGUGGUAUGUUCCGUGAUGAGCGUUUAGUGAGCCUGCUGGCUGCAGAGCACUAUGAAAUCAUGGUACGUAGUCCCCGGCACCUGUCGUUAUUCCUAUAUCCUCCUGCAACUGUGGUUUGAAACUGCGCAUUCUCUAGUAGUAUAUAUCGUGCCUGUCUUCAAAAACAUUUCCCUUUUUAUACUCAUUCCCCCCAGGCAUGGGGUAGUGUCAGUCGGACUGCACAGGGAACACGGUUUCCAGUGGCUUUGGCCCCUACUCGGGAAACGUCUGCCUGUUCUCGAUGGUGAUGGGGUGGCUGCCAUUCCCUUGGUUUUCCUAAGCCCUUUCUAACGAGAGUCUCAAACAAGCGGAGGCGAGGGCCAAUUCAACCCCAUUCUUUCCAGCGCCCCGCACCAUAGCACCUGCCCACCUGAGAACCAGGAACGCACCCUCUCUGUGGAGCUCUGACUGGUGUAGCUGGAAACAAACAGCAACUUGCAAACGGACGAAGAGCCUGCCGUGUGUUAAUCAUUUGCCUUACAAGAUGUACCAGACGGUUUCCAGUACUAACAAAGGGAAUAAAAAUACCUCACGCCACAAUCCAGCAUAUUGAUGUUUUAAGGCAAAACAACCAACUUUGUCUGUAGUCUUCAUUUUCUGUGUGGGGGGGGAGGGGGGAAGGGGACACUCCAGCAAGGGUUUCUAAAGCCCCAGUGUUCAGAGUGACACAGGGAGGGCCUGCCCCCCACUGUUCCCUAUGCUCCCCCCACCUCCAGGCAGGGGCAGAGCAAACAAACAGCUCCGGGCCACACAGCAGCAUCAGGCUCCCUCCAGAAGUCACCACUCACUCAUUCCUGGAGACUUGGGGACAAGGCAGUCUCCUCAGCUAUUUAUUUCUGAAUGAUUGAUUGAUUCCAAACUACUUGCUGGACACUGGUGGUUCUGACCUGUGACCAGCACCUCUGCUUCCUGUGUGCCCUCAAGAAAAUACUAGUGUGGGUAACAGUCCAUCUGAGUGGAGUUUGAGACACACUACACAUGAGACACACAAUGAUGCAGAUACUCGUUUUCUUGAGCUUUAUUGGCCCCUGCAUGAUACAGUCCCUGUGCUUAAGAACAUGCCCUAUUAGGUCACUCUGCCUUUGCUGACACAUUUUAUAGCAGAAAUACACAAGCUGUUUUUAAAGGAGGGAAAUAUAAAAAAUGUUUAUAAACUGACAGUGUUUUGCCAGAGGAAAGGUACAAAAUGCUACAUACAGAACCAAACCAGCCACUUCACAAGAGCAAUGCAGGGAUAAAACUAUUGGAUAAGGAAGGCAGAUGCACUUCCAAGAAAAUCAGAACCCAGCAAGAAGUGGCCAGUGCACCCCAAACCACACUGGUGUCCACCUCAUUGGCAGCAGCCAGCCAGGACACAGCUCAAAAACGCAGGAGCUACCAGCCACCCAGUCCACGGCCCUCGUCUCCCAGAGGCUGAGUACCUCCCCAGGCUGCAGGCUCUGGGCAGCUGAGCCAGGAGCAGCUCAGGGCUGGCACUGAGAGGCUACUGGUGACAGUAAACCCGUCUCAAAGGCUGGGCCUGGCUACAGACCAGCAGCAGUUGACGCUGAGGCAGGUUCCAGUGGUAGCCCUGGUGCCUGGGCUCUCUCUUAAUGCAGGCCUGGAAGUGGCGACACAAAAGCCAGCUUCCUUGGCUAAGAUGCCCUUAAAAACAUUGGGGCUGAUUUUGUGCGUCUACAGAAAGUAACAGCCCAGGAGAGAAUGUACACAGAGGCGAGCUUUCUAACUCCAUCAAACCCCACCUCCCCCGACAGGAAAUGCUGCCAGUCAACUCUAAAAGAACCACUUGUUGCUCUACGGGGGAAGGGGCUGAGUAUGAUUUGUCUGGCGACUGCAGAGACUCCCCGUUCAUACCAGUAUUCAUUAGAACCCAGUCCCUCGAGCGGCUCACCCACUGUUACUAGCAUGAGACUGGCUUCAGUGCUAAAAACUGUGAUGUCAUUGUCCAUUUGUAAAUCUGAAGAACUCUGUAAAUCAGAAAAGCUGCUGUCCGCCCUGGCUCACUUAAAAAUCAGGUAACGGCACACCCUGGGGAACACAGACUCAAUCUGUGUGAUUCGCAAGGACAAAACUCAUCUUUGACUUAUGCCGCCGGCCUCACGUAAGGAAACAGUUCCCCACACAGAAUACUCCCUGGAAACACAAAAUGAAAUCUUCUCCAAUUUUAUUAUUCAACAUAACAUUCUUGUAUGGAGUAAUGAGUACAAUAAGAAUUAGCAACUCAGUUCUAUUUCCCCAACCAAAAUAUAUCCCUUAUACAAAUUAAGAGUUCAACCCAAAUCCACUUCUAAUAAAAUACCUCAAUUUUAGAGCUUAAAAACCAGACUGCACUAGCAAACCGACACAAUAACCCACUCAAGCAUCUGUAGCUCAGGGCUCUGUCCCCUCCCUAUAGCUUAGAGGCCACUAGACCAGCAGAUAGCUGAGCUACAUCCCCAAGCUCACCCACUAACUUCCUUGCUUCCAAAAAUCCUGUCUUAACUCCACAAGAACUGGCACACCCACGGGAGAUGUCAAUCAUCAGCUUCAACAAACAUAAAAGAAUGCUUCAUGUACCAGUCAACAGCUGCUGCACGAACCCUCCCACUCCAGAAACCCAGAGAUUUUCCCCCUCGCCAAGCAAGGUCCCACAGCAAACCAAGAAAAACAGACACACUGGCUGCCUGCCUAGCAAGCAUAGGCCCCUUCCAGAGAAGCAAAAUAACUCUUAAGGUCCCCGGCAACCGCUACAGCAAUCGCACAGAUCAGCAACCUCCAACUGCAUCAUCUCGGUGAGCAAGUGCGCAAGCAGUCCAGGGCGCUGACCUGGGCACUCGGCAGCUCCAGGCCUGGGGACUUCUCCCUGGAGUCUUCCAAAGUGUCUCAUCACACACACACAGCCACGAGUACACACGCACGGCCACACAUACACAGCAGGUGCCCUGUCCUCUGAAGAGUCACAUUUCAAGGAGUAUGCAAAAUAAGCGUGUUAUAAAAUUUAUUUGUGUAAGCAUUCAGACAUUUUUAGGUGGGAAAGAUGAUAUGCAGAAUCCACUACAAGGUGCAACAGAAAAUCGUAUUGGAAAGGACGGUACAUCUGGCGCAGACCAGCAGUGGCACGAUUCCAAACAAAUGUCAGACGAGAGCGCUUCAUGGGGAGAAACUGAAAAUUAUAAUUUAAAGCUUCAUGAGGCAAGAUAUGUUCCAAUUUAAAACACUAAGAAAUAGUACCAUCGAUGAAAAAGGAAAUCAACCUCUAGGUGUACCAAAAGGGGCGUAGGGCAAACGGGGAAAAUUUGCAUUUGUUGAGGUACAAAUAGGAGUGUUCUGUAAGAGAGGGGCAUUAAUUAUUAAUGACAAACCCUGCAAAUACAAAAUAAAACCCAAAUCACUGGUCACAGAAUUCAAAAUGUACAUGUAAUAAAGGCAAGGCAAUAGACUCAAGUUAUGGCCUGUCGAAUAUUUACUCCACUGACGUUAUCUACAGAAGCACUUGGCCAGUUUGUACACAGUGAUUCCUUAUGCACGCCGAAAGGGUUUCCGUAAAAAUGACAUUAUAUACAAAUCUGUACACCCAUCCACCAGAGCGAUUCUCCAGCUCCCAGAGGGAGUUAUCAACUUAAAGCAGGAUACCUGAGGUUUCAUGUCUUUAGUUGCCUUAUCAUAAUCCCAAAUAUACAUUUCAGGGUUUGUUUUUGUUUUUAAAGACACUUUCCUGGAAUAUGUGCACUAUGGUUAAAAUUAAAAACAAAAGUAAUAAAAUAAAAUAAAAUGAUCGCUGGAAGGAGCUGACCCUCCCCACCCAUCUGAGAGACUUCAUCUGGCUGCAGCACAGUGAAGACUGUGUGUGUCCCUGGACGGGCGCCUGGCGCUGGGGUGGCUCCCAGUGGCGCACCUCUUCGGUGGAGUCAGCGAAGGCUCUCGUUGACUUUUAAAAAAGGAGGAGGAUGAAGAAGGAAAAAAGGAAAAACAAAACCCCAAAUGCCAAAGGAAUUUCAGUGGGAUGAAGUUCCUCCACCACUUAGAGAGUAUCUAGGGAAAAAGAGAGAGAGAGAAGUCAACACAUGUCAUUUCUCAUCCCUGUGCAAAAAUUCAUAUAGUAACCAAAAUCUUAGUUUUCAUAAGAAAUUCCAAGUCAUACAAAAAUAAGUGGAGCAAAUAUCAAUGUGUAAGUCUAAUUUUAAAAGAAUGCAUAUAAAGACUGAGAAGAUCAUGAUUCUUACACAAAAACUCCAGAGCAUGUCACCAAAAACCAAGAAUGGGUUCAGCCUCCCUGGAGAGAUGUGAAUAAAACGGGAAAUCAUAUCCCUUUUACUUACGAUCAAUUGUCAAAAAGUGAACAUUGAUCCAUACAUGAUGACACAGUAAGAUUCCAGGGAUGCAUAUGCAUUCCCGAUGUGAGGGCAGGAAACCCAUUUUGGCCAUAAAAAUAGUGAUGCAGUCCAAGAAUCUAUUUCCUAGAACUGCUUCCGAAAUAUGGUCCAAAGCAGGAACAACGUGUCUGCACAAAGAUGUCUCUCGGGAUUUUCGUAAUUACACUAAUUUGGAAACAACUCUGAUGCCCAACAGUACAGAAUCAGUUAAGUAAAUUAUACAAACUGAAAUAACAGACUAAAAAUGGUAAUUAUCUGUAUUUACAUAUAUAUAUUAAAGCAAUAUUAAAAAUAUGUACAAGUUUAAAAGUACAUACAAAAUUACAGAUUGGGCAUCCCUUAUCUGAAAUGCUUCUGGCUUUGGAUCUGGGAAUAUCCGCAUUAUACUUACCAGUGUGCAGCCCCAAAUCCGAAAUCUGACAUGCCCCAGAGAGCAGUUCCUUUGAGCCCCAUGCUGGCGCUCAAAAGUUUCAGAUUGGGGAUUUGGGAUAUUCAGCCUGUAUAUGUGCACUAUAUAAGUAUAUUUACAUGAACAACUUCUGUAUCCUAAAUUAAGUACUAUAGAAAUUCUAAAAAAUCUUCUUUGCACUAUAAGGUAGAUAAGAGAAUUCAGUAAGUUUAUGACCUGGUAUGACAACAGAAGGCAAUGCACCCAAAGAUGCUGAUGAGAUUUGGGCUACAGUGGUGGGAUCAUGGGUAAUUUCUGUGUCUUCCAAAAAUUCUACAAGAUUGUCUUCAGAAGACAACAAAGGGUGAGAACGGGGUCCCCUCAUGACCACAAUUCCCUCAACCAUUUUACAACAGACUCCAAAUCACAGGUCCAGGAGAGAUGGCUGAGGAUGUCUUUGACCAGGCUUAUCUCAAACGUUCCAAUCUAGAGCUCCUCUUUUCAGGCAUUUGAAAUACUUGGCAUCUCUCCCAGAGAACAAAUGGUUACAUAAGGUCCUCCCAAAAGCACACAUUAGCCACGGAGCCUAAGACUCAACUAUCAAGAAAUACAAAUGACUAAAUCACGGGAUGAGUUGAUGUCACACAAAAGAAUCCAAACAUUAAUUCCAGCUGAGACAGAAAGGCUCUGAAAAUGCUUCAGAGGAGAGGCGGCUCUCAUUUUUCCUACAGCCAUCCACUGAAACAACAUGUUUGGAGCAAAACUGGCAGGAAGUCUAAGCCAUGGCCACCGUGGUUUUGGCAGCCAUCGGGGUGAACGCUCAGUGGGAGCUUCAGGAGCAGGGAAGGAAGAAGUGGGUACCACAGCCAAGCCUGCAGAGAGAUGAUAAGCACCUCAAGAGGCAGCUCAUCUGAGGACAGAGGAGGAAAGAGGGCACUCCUCAUCACAGACAAAGGAAAGAGAGCACCAACUUGGCUUCCCCCAUGCAUCACUGCAAAGUAAAGUUUUAAACACAACACAGACAUCAGGUAGCUACAGACCCGCCCGAGGGUAAAUAGGGUCAACCCCAGCCACGAUGCCCAGUGAGCACGUAAAAUGUGCUGCGUCUGAAUGGAGAUGUGCUAAGUGUAAAACACACACCAACUCCAAAGACGGUCCCUCCAAAAAUGUAAAAUACCUUAUUGAUGAUUGUUGUUAUUAAUGUUGAAAUAAUACUUUGGAUCUGGCAGGUUAAAAAA